AUGAAUUUGCGUUUUCCAGGUUACUCCAUUGCCGCUAAAAUCACUGGUCCAACAACAGUGAAUGGCUCGGAGCAGGGCUCAUUGACUGUGCAGUGUGCUUAUGGCUCAGGCUGGGAGACCUACUUGAAGUGGCGGUGUCAAGGAGCUGAUUGGAAUUACUGUAACAUCCUUGUUAAAACAAAUGGAUCAGAGCAGGAGGUAAAGAAGAAUCGAGUUUCCAUCAGGGACAAUCAGAAAAACCACGUGUUCACCGUGACCAUGGAGAAUCUCAAAAGAGAUGAUGCUGACAGUUAUUGGUGUGGGACUGAGAGACCUGGAAUUGAUCUUGGGGUCAAAGUUCAAGUGACCAUUAACCCAGGCACACAAACUGCAGUCUCAGAAUGGACAACCACAACAGCAAGCCUGGCUUUCACAGCUGCAGCCACCCAGAAGACCAGCAGCCCCCUCACCAGGUCCCCGCUCAAGAGCACCCACUUCCUGUUCCUGUUCCUCCUGGAGCUGCCUCUGCUCCUGAGCAUGCUGGGGACCGUCCUCUGGGUAAACAGACCACAAAGAAGGUCUUGAAGGAGGAGGAGUCAGCCCGAUGAUGAGAGUCCCAAUGCCCAUUGACGUCCUGUCCAGGGCGAAAGGCCCUCCCACAGAAGAAAAAACAUUUUCUUUUCUCUUCUUUUUUUCUUUCUAGAGAUAGAGUCUUGCUCUGUCACCCAGGCUGGAAUGCAAUGGUGUAAUCUCUGCUCACUGCAACUUUCCCCUCCCAGGCUCAAGCGAUCCUCCUGCCUCAACCUCCAGAGUAGCUGGGGCUACAGGCACAUGCCACCACCCCCAGCUAAUUUUUAAAUUUUUUUGUAGAGAUGGGCUUCCACCACGUUGCCCAGGCUGGUCUCGAACUCUUGACCUCAAGAGAUCCUCCCGCUUCGCCUCCCAAAGUGGUGGGAUUACAGGUGUGAGCCACCGCACCUGGCAGAAAAACAACAUUUCUAUGGGGAAUUGACUGUGGUUCUAGAGGCAGUGCUGGCCCCAGCUUCAGGGAACAGCCUCCUAGUCCCCUAUCUCCUGCAGCCGUGCCACCUGGGGCUAUUCCCUUCUCUGCACAGUCCCUGGGGCCUGACAGAGCCCUUCUUCCUUCUGAGGUCUCCAAUGCAGUAGAAAACAUGAGAAGAAUGUGUUUCCCCCGAGAGGCACCUAUGCCGUAGUGGACAUUCGUGAUCUCAGGUCUGUGAGCCACAUGCAAUGUUAACGGACCUGUCUUUGCAUUCCGUGGGGUUCAAGUCUCCAGUCAAUAAUGGGUUUCAAAAUCCUAAACCCAUGAAAACAGAAAAACGGAACCAAACUCUGGUAAUGGGCCAACUUAAGGGAAGAUGAGUACAGAAGAGAGCAGAGGUUUCCGGGCUGCCGUGCCAGCUGCUCUCCUGCCACUUGUGGGGAAGGGAAGUCAGGAGAUUCCUGGAUGAGUACGAUUGAAGAUGAUGGGAAAACACAGCCUCCUUUCGUCACUGUAAGACUUUUCUAUUAGUGUUGAUUGUUACAUUUUCUUACCUCUUUUAAGAGUAUUGCAGUUGGCUGCUACUCUCAAUUUGGGGUAUAUGGGGAGAUCACCCAUACAUUUUGGGGACUGUGACAUAAUCCAUAAACUGGAUGCCAGAGCUAGAACUGUGAGCUGGGGAUGGCUGGGUCCUCAGUACCGCCUGCCUGGGUCCCCAGGGUGGUGCUCAGUCUUGGACUCUAAUGACUGAGCCCCCUGCCCAGUGGGAUCAUCUGGUGGUUAAGACAGAGGCUAAAUAACAGAAAUUCCCUUCUGGGAACAUGAACCAGGAUCACCCAACUGCCCUCUGUCAGGUCAAUCUCUGUACCCAGGUGAGACCCUUAUUCACUCCCCACCAUCAUUCAUUCCAAAAUGCUGGGCGCAGUGGCUCACUCCUGUAA